AGCCGCCAUCUUGGUCUAGGAGGGAGCGCGCCGCACGCGUGAGUAAACAGCCGGAGCUGGGAAAGUCGAGCUCUGGCAGCGUCUGGGUGCUGAGGGGCAGAGGCGGAGAGAACCCUGUCCUGAUCUUCCUAGGUGGGAUAAAUAUCGGGGUGACAGUGGUAGGCCGCGGGGAACCCUCAGUCUGCCCACCCUCCGCCCCCUCGCGGCGAGAUGCCUCGUUCCCCGGGCUUCUCCCGCCCUCCGCCGAUCUCCUCCCUCUGUUGAAAGCUGCCCGGGAAAGUGGUGGCGGGAGCGGGCCCAGGCCCGAAUGUGGCGUGGGCUCAGGUGUCUGGUGUCGGGCGCCGGAGGAGGUUCGCGCUGGGGUUUGGUGAUUCGGAGGCCUGGGGUGCAGACGCGGCGUGGCUGUGAGGCCCGGGCGGGCGUGCGGGUGUGAGGGCCGGACUCACACUGGGCCGCCGCGGGGCUGUUUCCAUCGGUCACUGGAUUUUCUCCUCUUCCGGUUCGGGCCUCAGGGUGGCCGACAUGACGGCCAGGGGUCAGAGCCCCCUCGCGCCGCUGUUGGAGACUUUGGAAGACCCUUCUGCCUCCCAUGGAGGGCAGACUGACGCUUACCUGACUCUGACCAGUCGUAUGACUGGAGAAGAAGGAAAAGAAGUAAUUACAGAAAUUGAGAAAAAACUUCCUCGGCUGUACAAAGUUUUAAAGACUCACAUUUCCAGUCAAAACUCGGAGCUGAGUAGUGCUGCUCUACAAGCCCUGGGGUUUUGCUUAUAUAAUCCCAAAAUUACCUCAGAAUUAUCAGAGGCAAAUGCUCUAGAAUUGCUUUCAAAAUUGAAUGAUACCAUUAAGAAUUCAGACAAAAAUGUACGUACUAGAGCACUUUGGGUGAUAUCUAAGCAGACAUUUCCCUCUGAAGUGGUUGGCAAAAUGGUAUCCAGUAUAAUUGAUUCAUUAGAAAUACUGUUUAACAAAGGAGAGACGCAUUCUGCUGUUGUUGAUUUUGAAGCAUUAAAUGUUAUCGUAAGGCUAAUUGAACAAGCCCCAAUUCAAAUGGGAGAAGAGGCAGUGAGGUGGGCAAAACUGGUCAUACCUUUAGUGGUUCAUUCAGCACAAAAGGUACAUUUGCGGGGAGCAACUGCUCUGGAGAUGGGAAUGCCAUUAUUGCUUCAGAAACAGCAAGAAAUAGCAUCUAUUACGGAGCAGCUUAUGACUACUAAAUUAAUCUCAGAACUUCAGAAGCUAUUUAUGAGUAAAAAUGAGACUUACGUGUUAAAAUUAUGGCCUUUGUUUGUCAAACUACUUGGAAGGACCUUGCAUCGAAGUGGGAGUUUCAUCAAUUCUCUCUUGCAACUAGAAGAACUUGGAUUUCGUAGUGGAGCACCCAUGAUUAAAAAGAUAGCUUUUAUUGCUUGGAAGAGUUUAAUAGAUAAUUUUGCUUUAAAUCCAGAUAUACUAUGUAGUGCAAAAAGACUCAAGUUGUUAAUGCAGCCUUUGAGUUCCAUCCAUGUGAGAACAGAAACUCUAGCAUUAACAAAACUAGAAGUCUGGUGGUAUUUACUGAUGAGACUUGGACCUCAUCUUCCUGCUAAUUUUGAACAGGUUUGUGUGCCUCUGAUUCAAAGUACAAUAAGCAUUGAUUCUAAUGCCUCACCUCAGGGCAAUUCGUGUCAUGUAGCUACAUCUCCAGGUUUAAAUCCUAUGACUCCUGUACACAAAGGUGCUUCCUCCCCGUACGGAGCCCCGGGAACUCCCCGAAUGAACCUGAGUUCGAAUUUAGGUGGAAUGGCCACAAUCCCAUCCAUUCAACUUUUGGGACUUGAAAUGUUGCUUCAUUUCUUGUUGGGUCCAGAAGCCUUGAGUUUUGCUAAGCAAAAUAAACUUGUGCUGAGCUUAGAGCCAUUGGAACAUCCGUUAAUCAGCAGCCCUUCCUUUUUUUCCAAACAUGCAAAUACACUUAUCACUGCUGUUCAUGAUAGCUUUGUUGCAGUUGGAAAAGAUGCCCCCGAUGUGGUUGUCAGUGCUAUCUGGAAGGAGCUAAUUAGCUUGGUGAAGUCAGUUACUGAAUCAGGUAACAAAAAAGAGAAACCAGGUUCUGAAGUUUUGACUCUCUUAUUAAAGUCUUUGGAAAGCAUAGUAAAGUCUGAAGUAUUUCCUGUAUCAAAAACGCUGGUCCUCAUGGAAAUUACAAUUAAAGGACUUCCUCAGAAAGUAUUAGGUUCACCAGCAUAUCAGGUUGCUAAUAUGGAUAUUCUUAAUGGAACUCCAGCUUUGUUCUUAAUUCAAUUAAUUUUCAACAAUUUCUUGGAAUGUGGUGUAUCAGAUGAAAGGUUCUUUCUCAGUUUGGAAUCACUUGUAGGCUGUGUUCUUUCUGGUCCAACUUCACCACUAGCUUUCAGUGACUCAGUUUUAAAUGUUAUUAAUCAAAAUGCAAAGCAGUUGGAAAAUAAGGAGCAUCUCUGGAAAAUGUGGAGUGUUAUAGUCACCCCAUUAACUGAAUUGAUUAAUCAGACCAAUGAAGUAAAUCAAGGUGAUGCCUUAGAACAUAAUUUUAGUGCCAUCUAUGGUGCAUUGACUUUACCAGUAAACCACAUUUUUUCAGAACAGAGAUUUCCAGUGGCCACCAUGAAGACUUUGCUUAGAACUUGGUCAGAAUUAUAUAGAGCAUUUGCUCGUUGUGCUGCUUUGGUGGCAACAGCAGAAGAGAACUUGUGCUGUGAGGAACUUUCUUCCAAGAUAAUGUCCAGUUUGGAAGAUGAAGGCUUUUCUAAUUUGUUGUUCGUGGAUAGAAUUAUUUAUAUUAUUACUGUAAUGGUUGAUUGCAUUGACUUCUCACCAUAUAAUAUUAAAUAUCAGCCCAAAGUUAAAUCACCACAGAGACCUUCAGAUUGGUCCAAAAAGAAGAAUGAGCCCCUAGGGAAAUUGACUUCUUUAUUUAAACUUAUUGUGAAAGUGAUCUAUUCUUUCCACACACUGAGCUUCAAGGAAGCACAUUCUGAUACCCUCUUCACUAUUGGCAACUCAAUCACCGGCAUUAUUUCCAGUGUACUUGGGCAUAUUUCUUUGCCUUCUAUGAUCCGAAAAAUAUUUGCAACUUUAACAAGACCUCUGGCAUUAUUUUAUGAAAACUCAAAGCUUGAUGAAGUUCCUAAAGUAUAUAGUUGUCUGAACAACAAGUUAGAAAAGCUACUGGGAGAAAUUAUUGCUUGUCUGCAAUUCAGCUACACCGGAACUUAUGAUAGUGAACUUCUUGAACAACUCUCCCCACUAUUAUGCAUAAUAUUUCUGCACAAGAAUAAACAGAUUCGAAAACAGAGUGCUCAGUUCUGGAAUGCCACUUUUGCCAAAGUGAUGAUGUUGGUUUAUCCUGAAGAGUUAAAACCAGUACUAACACAAGCCAAACAAAAAUUUCUGCUCCUGUUGCCUGGUUUGGAAACUGUUGAAAUGAUGGAGGAAUCCAGUGGACCAUAUUCUGAUGGAACAGAAAAUUCACAACUAAAUGUGAAGAUAAGUGGCAUGGAGAGAAAAUCAAAUGGAAAAAGAGAUUCAUUUUUGGCACAAACAAAGAAUAAAAAAGAAAAUAUGAAACCAGCAGCCAAACUGAAACUUGAAUCUUCGUCUUUAAAAGUAAAGGGUGAAAUUCUUUUGGAAGAGGAAAAGUCUACUGACUUUGUGUUUAUACCUCCAGAAGGAAAAGAUGCAAAGGAAAGAAUAUUAACUGAUCAUCAAAAAGAAGUUCUCAAAACAAAGCGGUGUGAUAUUCCUGCCAUGUAUAAUAAUCUGGAUGUUUCCCAAGAUACCUUAUUUACUCAGUAUAGUCAGGAAGAGCCUAUGGAAAUUCCUACUUUAACCAGAAAACCAAAGGAGGAUUCUAAGAUGAUGAUUACGGAGGAGCAAAUGGACAGUGACAUUGUCAUUCCUCAAGAUGUCACGGAAGACUGUGGUAUGGCUGAACAUCUUGAAAAGUCCUCCCUUUCGAAUAAUGAGUGUGGUUCUCUUGACAAAACCAGUCCAGAAAUGUCAAACAGUAAUAAUGAUGAAAGAAAAAAAGCUUUAAUUUCAUCAAGGAAAACAUCAACUGAAUGUGCAUCUAGUACAGAAAAUUCUUUCGUUGUCAGCAGUAGUUCAGUUUCUAAUACCACUGUUGCUGGAACUCCCCCAUACCCUACAAGUCGGAGGCAAACCUUUAUUACUUUGGAGAAGUUUGAUGGUUCAGAAAAUAGACCUUUUAGUCCAUCCCCCUUGAAUAAUAUUUCAUCAACUGUUACAGUGAAAAAUAACCAGGAAACCAUGAUUAAAACAGAUUUUCUACCAAAAGCAAAGCAAAGAGAAGGGACUUUUUCAAAAUCUGAUUCUGAAAAAAUAGUGAAUGGAACUAAGAGAUCAAGCCGGAGAGCUGGUAAAGCUGAACAAACAGGGAAUAAAAGGUCUAAGCCCUUAAUGAGAUCUGAGCCGGAGAAAAAUACUGAGGAAUCUGUUGAAGGCAUUGUAGUCUUAGAAAAUAACCCACCUGGUUUGCUUAAUCAAACAGAAUGUGUGUCAGAUAAUCAGGUUCAUCUUUCUGAAUCUACAAUGGAGCAUGACAAUACAAAGCUUAAAGCAGCAACAGUGGAAAAUGCUGUAUUAUUGGAAACUAAUACUGUAGAGGAGAAAAAUGUAGAAAUUAAUUUGGAAUCCAAAGAGAAUACACCCCCAGUAGUAAUAUCAGCAGAUCAAAUGGUAAAUGAGGAUAGUCAGGUUCAGAUAACUCCAAAUCAGAAAACCCUUAGACGGUCUUCAAGGCGACGUUCAGAAGUAGUAGAGUCUACCACUGAAAGCCAAGAUAAGGAAAAUAGUCAUCAAAAAAAGGAACGACGUAAGGAAGAAGAAAAACCUCUUCAGAAGAGUCCAUUGCAUAUAAAAGAUGAUGUGUUACCUAAACAAAAACUGAUUGCUGAACAAACUCUACAGGAGAAUUUAAUUGAGAAAGGAAGUAAUUUACAUGAGAAGACUCUUGGGGAAACUAGUGCUAAUGCAGAAACUGAACAAAAUAAAAAAAAGGCAGACCCUGAGAACAUUAAGUCUGAGGGGGAUGGUACCCAGGACAUUGUAGAUAAGUCCUCUGAGAAACUAGUCAGAGGCCGAACACGGUAUCAAACUAGAAGAGCAUCUCAGGGUUUGCUUUCCAGCAUUGAAAACUCAGAAUCUGAUAGUUCGGAGGCAAAAGAAGAAGGUUCUAGGAAGAAGAGAUCUGGAAAAUGGAAAAACAAAAGCAAUGAAAGUGUUGACAUUCAAGAUCAAGAAGAGAAAGUGGUGAAACAGGAAUGUAUAAAAGCUGAAAAUCAGUCACAUGAUUAUAAAGCAACUUCUGAAGAAGAUGUAAGCAUAAAAUCUCCGAUUUGCGAAAAACAAGAUGAAAGUAAUACUGUAAUAUGUCAGGAUUCUACAGUAACUUCAGAUUUGUUGCAAGUUCCUGAUGAUUUACCAAAUGUGUGUGAGGAAAAAAAUGAAACUAGCAAAUAUGCAGAAUAUUCCUUUACAAGUCUACCUGUGCCAGAAUCAAAUCUAAGGACUAGAAAUGCCAUUAAGAGAUUACAUAAGCGAGACUCUUUUGAUAAUUGUAGUUUGGGAGAAUCCUCAAAAAUAGGGAUAUCAGAUAUUUCUUCGCUUUCAGAAAAAACUUUUCAAACACUUGAAUGCCAACACAAGAGAAGUAGGAGGGUGAGGAGAUCUAAAGGUUGUGAUUGCUGUGGGGAAAAAUCACAACCUCAGGAAAAGUCACUCAUUGGGUUAAAGAAUACAGAAAAUAAUGACGUAGAGAUUAGUGAAACAAAAAAGGCAGAUGUGCAAGCACCUGUAAGCCCAUCAGAAACUUCUCAAGCUAAUCCAUAUUCUGAAGGACAAUUUUUAGAUGAACAUCAUAGUGUGAAUUUUCAUUUGGGUCUCAAAGAGGAUAAUGAUACUAUUAAUGAUUCAUUAAUUGUUUCUGAAACCAAAUCAAAAGAAAACACUAUGCAAGAAUCUCUUCCUUCUGGAAUAGUAAACUUUAGAGAGGAAAUUUGUGAUAUGGAUUCUAGUGAAGCAAUGUCUCUUGAAAGCCAGGAGUCACCUAAUGAAAAUUUUAAAACUGUUGGCCCGUGUUUAGGAGACUCGAAAAAUGUUUCACAGGAAUCUUUGGAGACAAAAGAAGAAAAACCAGAAGAAACCCCAAAAAUGGAACUGAGUCUAGAGAAUGUUACUGUUGAAGGAAAUGCAUGUAAAGUAACAGAAUCCAAUCUAGAGAAAGCAAAAACUAUGGAAUUGAAUGUAGGAAAUGAAGCUAGCUUUCAUGGACAAGAGAGAACCAAAACUGGUAUUUCUGAAGAAGCAGCAAUAGAAGAAAAUAAAAGAAAUGAUGACUCUGAAGCAGACACAGCUAAACUGAAUGCCAAAGAAGUAGCAACUGAGGAAUUUAAUUCAGAUAUUAGUCUUUCUGAUAAUACUACACCUGUAAAAUUGAAUGCUCAAACUGAGAUUUCUGAACAAACAGCAGCUGGGGAACUAGAUGGAGGAAAUGAUGUAUCUGAUCUACACUCAUCUGAAGAAACGAAUACCAAAAUGAAAAAUAAUGAAGAAAUGAUGAUCGGCGAGGCAAUGGCUGAAACUGGCCAUGAUGGUGAAACAGAGAAUGAGGGCAUAACUACCAAAACCUCAAAGCCUGAUGAAGCUGAAACAAACAUGUUGACUGCAGAAAUGGACAACUUUGUUUGUGACACAGUUGAAAUGAGCACUGAAGAAGGAAUCAUUGACGCUAAUAAAACUGAAACAAAUACUGAGUAUAGUAAAUCUGAAGAAAAAUUAGAUAACAAUCAAAUGGUAAUGGAAAGUGAUAUUUUACAGGAAGAUCACCAUACUUCACAGAAAGUGGAGGAACCAUCACAGUGUCUGGCAUCUGGAACAGCUAUCUCUGAGCUAAUAAUAGAAGACAAUAAUGCAUCUCCUCAAAAACUAAGGGAACUUGAUCCUUCACUUGUGUCAGCAAAUGACAGUCCUAGUGGCAUGCAGACACGCUGUGUCUGGUCUCCUUUGGCUUCUCCGUCUACGAGCAUUUUAAAGAGAGGACUAAAAAGAUCCCAAGAAGAUGAAAUCUCAUCACCUGUUAAUAAGGUUCGCCGUGUCUCCUUUGCAGAUCCAAUAUACCAAGCAGGAUUGGCAGAUGACAUUGAUAGACGGUGCUCUAUUGUUAGGUCCCAUUCUUCCAAUAGUUCUCCCAUAGGAAAAAGUGUUAAAACUUCUCCUACUACACAAUCUAAGAUUUCAGAAAUGGCCAAAGAAUCCAUACCAUGCCCAACAGAAAGUGUUUACCCACCAUUGGUGAACUGUGUGGCACCAGUUGACAUCAUUUUACCUCAGAUUACAUCAAACAUGUGGGCAAGAGGCCUGGGACAACUCAUUAGAGCUAAGAAUAUAAAAACUAUUGGUGAUUUGAGUACUCUUACAGCAUCUGAAAUAAAAACUCUUCCUAUCCGUUCUCCAAAAGUGUCCAAUGUAAAAAAGGCUCUCAGAAUAUAUCAUGAGCAGCAGGUGAAGACUCGUGGACUAGAAGAGAUUCCAGUUUUUGAUAUUUCUGAAAAAACAGUAAAUGGAAUAGAAAAUAAAUCUUUGUCACCUGAUGAAGAAAGACUUGUCUCAGAUAUAAUUGAUCCUGUUGCUUUAGAAAUUCCAUUAUCCAAAAACCUUCUGGCACAGAUUAGUGCUCUUGCUCUUCAGCUGGAUUCAGAAGAUCUUCAUAAUUAUUCAGGAAGCCAACUAUUUGAAAUGCACGAGAAACUAAGUUGUAUGGCAAACUCUGUAAUAAAAAAUCUACAGUCACGUUGGAGAUCACCAUCCCAUGAAAAUUCUAUUUAGUAUUUUCAGAGAAAAUUGAAGGUUUUUUUAAACAUCACUGGAUUUCUUGAUUGAGGAAACAAGUUCUGAAAUAAUAGCACAAUUUCAAAGAAGAGACUCUUUGCAAAGUUGAUAACAUUUCAAACCCUGAAGGACAGUGACUUAUUAUGUAAGUUCAAUUUUGUAAGUUCAUUAUGUAAGAUCCUUUUUUUUUUCAUAAUAUGUAUUCUUGGCUGCUAUGCGUGGUUUUUCAGGAAAUUUAAUUAUCUUACUGAGAUGUGAAAGCAAAACUAGUAACAGAACUUACAUUUUAUUUCAUGCUUUCUUAAACCCGUGCAUAUUCUGGUGAAACAUGUAAAAUACUUUAAGUAAAAUUGAACAUUUUUAUUUGAAUUUUUGCUGAACUGAUAAAGGUGUUUAUAUUUUUGUUUGUUGGUUUGUUUAAUUCAUGUUUGUUGGGACUGAGGUUUAGGAAGUUUGUUACUGGUUAAAAACCUCAAAUGAAAUGCGAAAGAAUUUGAAUUUUUCCUGCAUAUGUCAACUUUGGACAGCUUUCAAGAAAAAUGAGAAAAGUUUCAACUUCUGGCGGUUAAAAUAUUAAUGCAGAAUUUACUAAGAUUUUAUUCAUUUGCAUUAGCAAAUAUUCAUGCAGCAGCAGUUGACUGAAAAUUUAUUCUUAUGAGACGUAUAGUAUUCAUUUUUAAAUGCAUGAUUGUACAUUAUGUAUAGACGACAAUGUUUUUAAUUUAUAAAUUUCAUUCUUUGUUAAUUGCAUGGGUUUUUCUGCAGCUUAUUGUGAAUACCUUGGUUCUGUUCAAUAGAAACAUUUUGUAUAUAUUAAAUACUGAAAUAUCAGUAUCGACGGUGGAAGUGCUUCAUGGGCUUGCUGCACAUAUUUGUAGGAUACUGUAUCUGCAAAUGCAACAACAAAUAGUUUUGUACUUGGUUAACAGUCUUAGUUAAAACAUGAGUUUAUUUUCUAAAAGUAUCCAGAAUAAGUAAAAUUAUAGAAAUAAGAAAAUGUUACACAACUUUGCUGUUCAUACCCUUACCUUCUUACUACUUUUGGUUUGGAGGAGGGUAUCACCACUAGAAAGUGUGCCUCCUUAAGAUUUCUUAAAGGAAAGUUAGUUUCAGUAUUUCACAGCAAGUUGGACUACAAAAUCUAGAGUUGAUCUGCUUUUUAAACCUUCAUUUAAAAGCAAACUUGGAAGAAAUUUGAAACUGAUGUUUUUAAUAUAUGUCUGUGUUGCCUAGGUUUUCUUUUUUUAAAGAGGUAUGUAAUUAAAACCUUUGUAAAAUUUGCCAACUAAUAUUAGUGCCUGACUUCCCAUAUUUGUUUCAUCUUUUUAACUGACAGUAUAUCUCACUUCUUCUUUGAAUAGAAUGAGUGAGUGAUCUCAGUUUUCACAUUUUAUUCAGAAGCUAAUCCCUACUUAGCAAGGCACACAUUCUACAGCAAGUCAUAGAAAGUUUAAUCCUUGUGCCUCCUUAGCUCUCGUAUAUUCAGGGAUCUCUAUAAAAGUUGGUGUCUUUUUUCAUCAUCAUAAAUUCAUCAUAAUCACAGAUAUUUUUGGGUCUAAGAUAUUCAUAUACCAAGGAUGGUUUUGUAAAGAAUUCUGGGAUCAUUGAAUUAAGGAUUGUGGCUUGAAGUAACUAAAGAAAAAUACUAAUUUCCUUAAAAGGAAUUAUAAUUAUGAUUUACAUUUUACAUCAUUAAUUUCCCAAAUUAUAUUUAACCGUAAGGAGGUGCACAUGAGUUUUUAGCAAACAGGUAUGAAUAAGCAGCUAUGUAUAUGUGUUUGGGGCAGAGGGGAGCAGAUUACUUUAACACACUUCAGAAUUAAAAUCAGUUCGUUUCAUGACUCUGUGCCUUAACGUUUGUGUGAACUAAACUUGCUGAUUGAAUGAAAUUCUUGGGAAGCCGAACAGUAAUAGCAGAAAAUGUGACCAAAUGAGUAUCAUGUACUUAAAUCACUGAAUUUUAUAUAAGCACAAGUAUUAAUUUUAAAAACAUUAUAGUUUAAUAAAGCUGCAUUUAAAAAUAUUUGGGAGCAAAGACAAGCAUGCUAAAUCUUCAUUUUGCUAUGGCUAUAAGCAUAUAUUUUUGGCAACUUAUUUGCAAUAUUCUUGCCUUAAAGUUUCCUGCAAAUUUCCCCCUUAGUAAUUCCCGAAUAGCAAAACAUUAAUAUUCCAUGAUUAGCUCUACUGUGUUGUCUCACUAUUAAAAUGGAAUUCGUUUUUUCAGAUCUUUUCUAAUGGUUAAUAAAACAAAUGUCAGAUCAUAAUAACACUCAAAUGUGUCUUAAUUGUCUUAUGCAUAUUUAAGAAGAAAAAACUAGUGGCAUACAGGAUUGUCAUGUAGUAUCUUUUUUUUUUUUUGAGACACAGUCUUGCUCUGUUGCCUAUGCUGGAGUGCAAUGGUGCGAUCUCGGUUCACUGCAAGCUCUGCCUCCCAGGUUUACACCAUUCUCCUGCCUCAGCCUCCCAAGUAGCUGGGACUACAGGUGCCCGCCACCAUGCCCGGCUAAUUUUUUAUAUUUUUAGUAGAGAAGGGGUUCACUGUGUUAGCCAGGAUGGUCUUGAUCUGACCUCGUGAUCCGCCUGCCUCGGCCUCCCAAAGUGCUGGGAUUACAGGCGUGAGCCACCCCACCUGGCCAUUUUCUUUUUUUUUUGAGGUGGAGUUUUCGCCCUUGCUGCCCAGGCUGGAGUGCAGUGGUACGAUCUCAGCUCACUGCAACCUCCACCUCCUGGGUUCAAGCGAUUCUCCUGCCUCAGCCUCCCAAAUAGCUGGGAUUACAGGUGCCUGCCACCACCACUGGUUAAUUUUUGUAUUUUUAGUAGAUACGGGGUUUCACCAUGUCAGCCAGGCUGGUCUCAAACUUCUGACCUCAGAUAUCCACCUGCCUCAGCCUCCUAAAAUGGUGGCAUUACAGGCGUGAGCCACCGCUCCUGGCCCAUCAUUUCCAUAUCUAUGAAAUCUAUUUUGGAUUUUAGAGUGGAUUUAAAUUUUCAAUAUUUCAGUGACCUCAUUGUUAAAGCUGCUUUGCCACUUGUACAAGUUUGAAAACCAUUGUUGAAUCAUAUGGAGCUUUACUCUAAUUCCAAAUAGUUAAAGGAUGAAUCAGGUUAAAUAAUGCUGUUGGAUAAUACAGGCAAAAACAGGAUUUAAACCCGCACAUUAAAAGCAUGACUGAAGGCCCGGCAGGUGGAUCACUUUGGCCCAGGAGUUCAAAACUGACCUGAACAAUGUGGCGAAAUCCUGUCUCUACUAAAAAUACAAAAACCAGCCAGGCAUGUUGGCGCAUACUUGUAAUCUCAGCUACUCAGGAGGCUGAGACAUGAGAAUUGCUUGAACCUUUUAGGCGGAGGUUGCAGUGAGCCGAGAUCAUGCCAUUGCGCGACAGAGCAAGUCUCUGUCUCGCAAAAAAAAAAAAAAAGUUUAAUUCUAACAUUGCCCAUGGAUUUUUUUUUUUCUGUACAGCUUGAAGAUAAGAUAGUUAAAGACUCUGUUACAAUUUAAACAUCAUAAAAAUGUGAAGAGUAAGUGGUGAGGCAAGAAACAAAAUUGGGGGAAAUGGUGGGGAUCGUGAAUAUAUAAGUGAAGUUUUAUUUUUUUAAGGUGUAAAGGAGUGAGAAUAGAGUAAUUGCUUUUUAAAAAGAAAGUAUAAAUGGGUUAAUUUUUUUCUUCCAACUUUGACUUUAAUUCAGUAAGAAAGGCCUAGGUUUCAUCUCAUAUUCUUCAUAAUUGAUUUUCAAGAAGUUAAUUUGUCAUUCAGCCUAGGAGGCUAUAAAACAGCAGUUAGUUGGCAUUAUUAGACUAAAACUUGGGUGGGGGGAGGAGACUGUUUCCUCAUUGCUGCAACCCAUGGUCUAUCCUAUUCCUAAGCCAUUAGAAAGACCUUGUACUUUGUAUAGAAACAUUAGAGUGAGGUUUUGAUUUUUAACAUAGUACUCUCAAACUUUGAUGUGCAUAUGAACAAGUGGAUUCUGAUUCAGUAGAUCUGCAUUGGGCCCCGUGAGUCUUUUUAAACACAGUCCCAGGUGAUUCAUGCAGAUGCCUGUGAACUGCGCUGGUAGAUGGGCCUAAGAGGCUUCAGGCUGUGUUUUAGGUUUUGGUAAGCCAGGCAGAUUCAAGUCCUUUUAUAACUGUCAAUUUUGUGAAUUGGGGAUGCAGACUGGUUUUGAAGGCUUAAAGUUCAAAAAUUAUAAGAAAGUUAAGAAUUUUGCUUAAGAGCCUUUUAAAAAUAUGGACGAUUUAUUUUUUAAGUAGGCAGACUAAGAAUUUCAAGUUAUAAAGAAUCUUAUUGAUAAGGCAAAGUAGACAAAGUAUUUUCUCAUGAGUAUUUGUGGGUUAUGUUUUUGUUAAUAUAAAAGUUGAUUUCUAAGUAUUAGAAUAUAUUUAGUCUCUAAAUAAAUCUUGCCUUCUAUUAUGGAUCAUCGUUAUUAAUAAACAUGGAAAAUCAACACUACCCCUAAUAUUAAUCUGGCAGUUAAAUUUAGUAGUGCUAUAAUGAAUAAGUCAGUCUAGCAGAUAUGCCCUGUCAUUAUACUGCGGACCUCUGGUCACUUAAUUUUCUGUUAUAUUAUGUGGUUGAAAAUUCCUGUUUCAUCGUAAAGUGAAAUUUGAAAGAUGGAGUUGAAUAAUAUGAUUCUCGAAAAGUGAGUUUUUCUUGGAAUUCUGUUAAGGUGUUAGAUUUUCCUCACAUAUUUAAAUAAUCUGUAAGAACUACCCUGAAAGCACUAAGGAAAAUGUAGCCGAAAGUUAAGUAAUAGGUUUUAAAAAUUUAUCAAAAUUUAUUGAUAGUUUGAUCUGUAAAACAAAUUGGGUUUCGUGCUUUCUGAUGUCCAGUUAAUAAGUAUAUUAUGUGCCAGGCUUUACAUAUUGCUCUUUGCAAGUAGCCGUUAAAGUGUAAGUCAUUGAAGUUUGAAGAUCUAUAAAUAUUUAAUAUAGUAGUCUAAACAGUUGUGAGAAUUUACUCAGUUCUGAAAUAGAAUGUUAAAUUUUCCGAUGUGGUCCUAAUCAUUUUUUUCUUUACAUACUAAGCCUUCCUUUCUCCAAAGAACAGUUAAAACCAAAUGUGUUAUGGUAAGCUGUAAAUACCGUUGGAAUAAAAGAUAACCGUUCAUCUUACCUAAAAAAUUGAAGACAAUAUUUUCCAUUGUUGAUGUCACAAGUAAGAAAAAAACUCUAACUUUUGUACUCUACUUGUAGCAGAGGGAAUAUUUUUGGCCACAGUGUGCCAAUUUAUAAUUGUAGAUAAAGCUGAAUUUACUGGGCAGCAAGCUUAUAUGCUGAUAGAAGUUGAUGCACUGAGAAGUGAUGAGUUGAAGAGAAUGGAAAAGGCAGAUUGAGCUGGAAUUUUAAUGCAUAGUACAUUUAGUAGAGAGACAAGCUGUCCUAUAUACUCCUGUAUACUUCAGAAAUAGCUGAUAGCCUAUAGUCUCUGAGAGCUAUUCUGUACAUAGCACAGUAUUAUAAUUGAUGUUCAUAAAUACCCUGAGAGAUUAUGUUAAAAUACAUUAUUAAUACUCCCACAAAAGCAGUAAGUUAAUAAGUAUUUCCAACAAAAGGCAGCUUUGUUUCUUAAACGGAUAAACAACAUAUAACUAGGAAGAUCAUCUUCAAAAUAAAGUGUCAUGGAACUGAAAAUAGAGUAUAGUCUAACAAUUAUUUUGAUACACUAUUGAAUAGCUAACAAGUGUCUAAAGAAUUUUUUAUUUUUAUAGAAUAGGAAGUUUCUAAAAGAAAACAAUUAAGAGCAAAAUUGGUUUUGAGUAUAGAAACUGAAGGAUGGCAGUCUUAACUCCUAAGUUUUUUACAGAGCACAGAUUGGUAAACUAGCAUGCCACCUGUUUUUUGUACUAUCUGUGAGCUGAGACUGGUUUUUACAUUUUUUAAUGGUGAAAAAAGUCAAAAGAAGGACAUUUUGUGACACAUGAAAACAUAUUAAAUUAAAAUUUCAGUAUCCAGAAAUAAAGUUUUAUUGGAACAGCUGUGCUUAUUGUCUUUAGCUGCUUUCCUGGUACAGUGGCUGAGUUUAGUAGUAUAGCAGAGUCUGUAUGGCUUCCAACAGUCAAAAUACUGCCUGGCCUUUUAAAGAGUUUGUCAAUCCCUUUUAUGGAGGAAGGUUUUGCUCAUGCAUGGCAUGUUAGUCAAUUUAGUUAUUUGCUUCUAGCUGGCAGAAUGUGGUCUUGAUUACUUAAUUUCUGUUACCCCUGUGUUUUCCAGAAUGGCUUCUCCUGAUUUUACUUACGUGUUUUACUAUUGCUCAAAUUACAGAUACUAGGAAACACUACUACUUUAUAAGUACACUUCUUUUUCCUACUUAAACUCUCAAACUACAGUUACGUAUUUGCCAUGAUGUUAAGGGACCUUGAUGGUCUGUGAAUUAUCAGUUGCUUUCUGCACUACCUCCUGUAGAUAGACCUGACUGAUAGCACUUACAAAAAGACUGAUAGAUGCCAAAUCAGUCAUUUAUUAACCCUCUAAUAUUGUUGUCCCGAUCAUUUGGUAAACGCUAAGAGAGCUUAGUUUUACAUUCACAAAGUAUUUGUAUUUGAUAAGUCUUAAAAAUGAUUUAAGUUGAAGCCUAACAGAAGUACUUGUUCAUUCCUCAGUUACCUGCAAAUAAUGGAAAUAAUGGUGCAGUCAGUUUUAUUUGAUUGUGUAAUGCUUUAUACUAGGGGUCUCAAACCCCUGGGUGGCAUUAGAUUCUUACAGGAGCGUGAACCCUAUUGUGAACUGCACAUGCAAGAGAUCUAGGUUGUGCGCUCAUUAUGAGAAUCUAAUACCCGAUGAUCUGAGGUGGAACAGUCUCAUCCUGAAACCAUCUACCCCAACACCUGUGUCUGUGGAAAUUGUCUCCACGAAACCGGUCCCUGUUGAAAAAAGGUUAGGGGACCACUGCUUUAUACAGUGUUUGAAGUAGGCACACUUACAGUUACUAUUUCUGGUUCUUUAUGACUGUUGAGGGGGGGCAGAAUUCUAUGUUUGAUUCACAGUAAAACUUUUCAUGAAUCAUUGAGGGUUAACUGUUAUCACUUGCCAAUGGAAACUGGAUAUUGAAACAUUUUUUUAAGAAAUGCACUUUUACCUGAAAUAAAACUAUAAAAACUAAA